GAAUUGCGCUUCCGCCAUCUUUCCAGCCUCAGUCGGACGGGCGCGGAGACGCUUCUGGAAGGAACGCCGCGAUGGCUGCGCAGGGAGAGCCCCAGGUCCAGUUCAAACUUGUAUUGGUUGGUGAUGGUGGUACUGGAAAAACGACCUUCGUGAAACGUCAUUUGACUGGUGAAUUUGAGAAGAAGUAUGUAGCCACCUUGGGUGUUGAGGUUCAUCCCCUAGUGUUCCACACCAACAGAGGACCUAUUAAGUUCAAUGUAUGGGACACAGCCGGCCAGGAGAAAUUCGGUGGACUGAGAGAUGGCUAUUAUAUCCAAGCCCAGUGUGCCAUCAUAAUGUUUGAUGUAACAUCGAGAGUUACUUACAAGAAUGUGCCUAACUGGCAUAGAGAUCUGGUACGAGUGUGUGAAAACAUCCCCAUUGUGUUGUGUGGCAACAAAGUGGAUAUUAAGGACAGGAAAGUGAAGGCGAAAUCCAUUGUCUUCCACCGAAAGAAGAAUCUUCAGUACUACGACAUUUCUGCCAAAAGUAACUACAACUUUGAAAAGCCCUUCCUCUGGCUUGCUAGGAAGCUCAUUGGAGACCCUAACUUGGAAUUUGUUGCCAUGCCUGCUCUCGCCCCACCAGAAGUUGUCAUGGACCCAGCUUUGGCAGCACAGUAUGAGCACGACUUAGAGGUUGCUCAGACAACUGCUCUCCCGGAUGAGGAUGAUGACCUGUGAGAAUGAAGCUGGAGCCCAGCGUCAGAAGUCUAGUUUUAUAGGCAGCUGUCCUGUGAUGUCAGCGGUGCAGCGUGUGUGCCACCUCAUUAUUAUCUAGCUAAGCGGAACAUGUGCUUCAUCUGUGGGAUGCUGAAGGAGAUGAGUGGGCUUCGGAGUGAAUGUGGCAGUUUAAAAAAUAACUUCAUUGUUUGGACCUGCAUAUUUAGCUGUUUUGGAACGCAGUUGAUUCCUUGAGUUUCAUAUAUAAGACUGCUGCAGUCACAUCACAAUAUUCAGUGGUGAAAUCUUGUUUGUUACUGUCAUUCCCAUUCCUUUUCGUUUAGAAUCAGAAUAAAGUUGUAUUUCAAAUAUCUAAGCAAGUGAACUCAUCCCUUGUUUAUAAAUAGCAUUUGGAAACCACUAAAGUAGGGAAGUUUUAUGCCAUGUUAAUAUUUGAAUUGCCUUGCUUUUAUCACUUAAUUUGAAAUCUAUUGGGUUAAUUUCUCCCUAUGUUUAUUUUUGUACAUUUGAGCCAUGUCACACAAACUGAUGAUGACAGGUCAGCAGUAUUCUAUUUGGUUAGAAGGGUUACAUGGUGUAAAUAUUAGUGCAGUUAAGCUAAAGCAGUGUUUGCUCCACCUUCAUAUUGGCUAGGUAGGGUCACCUAGGGAAGCACUUGCUCAAAAUCUGUGACCUGUCAGAAUAAAAAUGUGGUUUGUACAUAUCAAAUAGAUAUUUUAAGGGUAAUAUUUUCUUUUAUGGCAAAAGUAAUCAUGUUUUAAUGUAGAACCUCAAACAGGAUGGAACAUCAGUGGAUGGCAGGAGGUUGGGAAUUCUUGCUGUUAAAAAUAAUUACAAAUUUUGCACUUUUUUGUUUGAAUGUUAGAUGCUUAGUGUGAAGUUGAUACGCAAGGAAAAUGGUCCAUGUUUACCCACAGUUUUCAGGUACUCCUAGACUUUAAAGAUGUCUUGAACAUUUAAGUUCUUCAGCAGUUCACACUACACCGUUUUUUUGUUUUUUUUUCCCCCCCGGGAGGGUUUUUUUGUAGGGCAGCACAGCAGAGCAGGACAUGGAUGAAAUACUAGGAAUAUGCACAGUGGGGCAGUGUGGGGGCUUCUCAGUAAUGGAGAACAGUUGGUGAAACUUUUUUUUUUUUUUAACUAAGCAUUUAAUUUAUCUUGCAUAUUUUCCACAUUUAAAAAUGAAUUAGGUCUAUUAGGAUAAUUAGGAGUUUGAUCCCAUCAACACUAUUCUUGUAGCAGUUAGGAAUCUUGAGCUAUUUUUUUCUCAUACGAUUACUAUAGUCCAGUUUACCAAAGUUUUCUUUAGAUGUCUGAUAAUCUUGAGAUGAUUGCUUACCUUAAAAGGUAUAGAAAGGAUCACUUAAAUAUAUGGAAAAAUGAAAUAAGGGUGAAGCUGAAUAAAGUUCUACUUACUGUAUUAACUGGCAACAGUUGAGUUUCUUAAGAUCUGAAUUGCUGUGUAUGUUACGCUGUAUUCAGAACCAGUUUCUAACCAGCCUGUGAGAUGGGAAGUUUUUUCCCCAUAAUUGGGAUGAAACCUUUCAUUCAGGUAUUUUGAAUUGAAGGUGUAUGUGUUGUUUGUAACCUUGUGGAGAUUGCAAGUGGUGUUGACAUUCUGGAUCUUCUAUGUAACAGUUGAAAUUUGGAAGUGACGUCACUUACCUGUCUAACGUGGUGUGGGAGAGAAUUUACAAGUCCUUUAUUGAAAGAAUAAUUGUUGCAAAAUAUAUUGCUUCUACUUUGCCUGGA